GUUCCCUGUUCUCGCCUGCAGCUCCGCCAUGGCUCCUAAAGGCAGCUCCAAACAGCAGUCUGAGGAGGACCUGCUCCUGCAGGAUUUCAGCCGCAAUCUCUCGGCCAAGUCCUCCGCGCUCUUCUUCGGAAACGCGUUCAUCGUGUCUGCCAUCCCCAUCUGGUUAUACUGGCGAAUAUGGCAUAUGGAUCUUAUUCAGUCUGCUGUUUUGUAUAGUGUGAUGACCCUAGUAAGCACAUAUUUGGUAGCCUUUGCAUACAAGAAUGUGAAAUUUGUUCUCAAGCACAAAGUAGCACAGAAGAGGGAGGAUGCUGUUUCCAAAGAAGUGACUCGAAAACUUUCUGAAGCUGAUAAUAGAAAGAUGUCUCGGAAGGAGAAAGAUGAAAGGUUUGACUCCUGUUUAAAGUAUGGCCAUCAUAAAAGGGGAAUCUUGUGGAAGAAGAAUGAAGUUGCUGAUUAUGAAGCUACAACAUUUUCCAUCUUCUAUAACAACACUCUGUUCCUGGUCGUGGUCAUUGUUGCUUCCUUCUUCAUAUUGAAGAACUUCAACCCCACAGUGAACUACAUAUUGUCCAUAAGUGCUUCAUCAGGACUCAUCGCCCUCCUGUCUACUGGCUCCAAAUAGACCAUGUCAGCUUCACCCCCUGGCUUUGUGUCUAUGGGUGGCCUGUGGUAUAUGGAAAAGUAGCAGGGUGGUCAGGGUGGGAGACACAAGAUGUUUUUAUAGUCUAGAGCCUUUAAAAAACCCAGCAGAAUGUAAUUCAGUAUUUGUUUAUUGGCUGUUUUUUGACAGAUUGUUGAAAUUAAAUGAAUUGAAAGGGAAACUCAGAGUACUAGGACGUUUAUUAAAAGGAAAAAAAUGUCUUGCAAUGUGCUGUAAUCACAAGAGGAGAAAAUAACUUGUUUCCUUGAUCUGUCAGAGGUCACAGUAACCUGGGCCGAGCUGUUAUUAUUUAUUAUAUAAUAGUAGUAGGAAGUUAAUAACUGGUUCUCUGUGUUCCAAGCACAAUAUUACAACUUCUUUUGAACCGUAAAUAUCAGAAUGAAUCCUCUUCCCAGGGGAUUGAACAGAAGCUUAAUGUUUACAAGUGUUUGAAUUUGUGAUCUGAAAUAACACAAAAUUAAAAACAUGAUUUCUCUAAUUUUCCAACUAGAGGAAGAGAAACUUGUGGAAAAGUUCUUUUUUUUUCUUUUUUUUUUCUUAAAGAAGGGCAGCCAAGGUAGUAACCUAAAAAUAGUGCCCAGGCAUAUGAGAGUUGUCCUACGAGGUUAAAGAACACACUGUUCCACUGUAUGGCUUUGGCCCUGAGUGGCCAGGGAGGUCAACUUGACCCUGCCAUGUUGGUUUGACUUACUAAGACACAGGAAUCACUGUUUUCCUUGACCAGGGUCUCACACCCUGGAGGAAUGUUAAGUAAGAGAAAGAACCUCUUUCCUGAAUAUUGACAUGUAAAAGACCAAAGUAAUUUUUCUGAACUUCUGCAAUUCUGAGAACUCUCCAAGGAAUUUACAGUGAUUUUAGUGCUUGUCAGCAUUUUUCCAUGAGGACUUUCAUACAUUUGACUCUUUAGUUCACAGGUUCCCAUUGAUUGUGAGCAAGAUAUUUAUCUCUUUAGCCCUUGGGGAUCCAGCUGAGAGCAAUCUCUUGCAUUUUUUUACCCGUGUAUGUACAGAUAUCAUUUCUUGUGUAUGCCAUGACUUGAAAAAGUUUGGGAAGCUCUUUAGCAAUAUCAGCUAAAAGGAUAUGAAAUCACAGGUGAUAGCAGUUGUCAUUCAGUAAUUUCCUACAAGCAGCACCCCAAAGGAAAUAUAGUCCUAAUCUUUACUAUCCACUUCUAAAUUUAAUGUGAAUUUCAUACAUGUUAUUAGUUGUUUUCUUUAUAAUUUUAUAAAAAUUAUUCAUCGGGAGUUUAACUUCCACUUCCAUGCUAUCGGAUGUGUUGGGCUCCAUGCAAGAACUUGGAAGAAAAACAGGCAGGAAUGCAUUUGCAUAAUGACCCAGAUCAUCAUUUUCUGCAACUGAGAAUUAUAUUUCAUCAUUGCUUCUAGAAGUCUGCAAUUCUUUACUUUUCUUUGGUGCAUUAUUAUCUAGGUGCCAUCACUGGAUAAUGUGGAGUGACUAGAGAAGUCACAUAUCACUGUAAGGUACAGUUAGGGUAACACUUUAGAGGUUUAUUAUUUUUAAAAAACUUUUCUUGAACUCCUGGCCAACAUGGUGAAACCCCGUCUCUACUAAAAAUACCAAAAUUAGCCAGGCGUGAUGGUGGGCGCCUGUAAUCUCAGCUACUUGGGAGGCUGAAGCAGGAGAACUGCCUGAACCCAGGAGGCAGAGGUUGCGGUGAGUCGAGAUCGUGCUACUACUGCCUGGGUGGCAAGGGUGAGACUCCAUCUCAAAAAAGAAACAAAAAAACCCAAAAAGUUUUCUUUACUGUUGGUUAAAAAAAAAAGCCAGACCAUAGUUUGACUGGUGGCAUGGAAUUUGUGUAUCAAAUAAAUGCAUUUGCUUAUUUGACAAACCAUCAGUGUCCACUAUUUGUUACCAGAGUUGGGCCACUAUCUUUUAAAAUUGCUGGUGAAAACUUGCCACUAGAUGGCAGUGCCUGUAUAGAUGGGGAAAAAAUUGCCACCAUUCUUGGUAUAAUACAGUGUAGCUUAGAUGAGGUGGUGAAAUAGGGGUAUCAGCCGAAUAUUCCUAAUAUAGUUUCUCUUGAAUUAAUAAACUGAAGAUUUGUAGGAAAAUGAGUGAGCAAAAUUUGUUUACUGUUGUGAAUUUUUCCUACAGCACUGUUUUUAAUCUUGAUGUUUUCCAACUUUCUGUACUAAUAGAUACAUUUCUGUGCAUAAGAUUAUAAAGCAUAUACUCACAGUUCAGUAGUUUUCGUUAAGGAUUUACUGUGUGAGUACUUUACUGUGAGGAAUUGCAGAACCUUUUCCCCUCUACUCUUGUCUAAAAGUUCUGUGUGGCACACAGAGAUGCGACCUACUCAAUCUGACUUAGUAAAACCAUGCUGUAGAAUUUUUGUCUUAAAAAGACCACAUACCCAGCACCCAUGAAAUAAAAGAUUCAUCUGUAAUUGGGAUUCAAAGUGAUUAAAUUCCUUUGUUCAUACUCAUAAAUAGCACUAAAGUGUUAUAACAUUUUCAUUUACCUAUUUUUAGUUCCUUCAUUUUAACUUAAUAAAAAUCUUGGAUUGAUAUUCUUUUUUUUUUUUUUUUUUUUUUGAGACAGCGUCUCGCUCUGUCACCCAGGCUGGAGUACAGUGGCUCUAUCUUGGCUCACUGCGAGCUCCGCCUCCCAGGUUCACGCCAUUCUCCUGCCUCAGCCUGCCGAGUAGCUGGGACUACAGGCGCCCGCCACCACACCCGGCUAAUUUUUUUGUAUUUUUAGUAGAGACGGGGUUUCACCCUGUUAGCCAGGAUGGUCUCGAUCUCCUGACCUCGUGAUCCACCUGCCUCGGCCUCCCAAAGUGCUGGAAUUACAGGCGUGAGCCACCGCGCCCGGCCUAGAUUGAUAUUCUUAAGCAAUAAAAGUUUACUGGUUGUCCUAUUUGCCAUAUUAUUGAAACUUGGAAAGGAUAAUUUGAAACAAGGUUUGAAGUUAACUGAAAUAUGGAGAUUGAAUUUAUACUCAAUUCUUGUGAAAAGUCUUGCUUAAUAAGUAUGAUUAAACUUUGCUUCUUAAAAUUUGUAUUUUCCCUACACUUCUUUAUAAGAAUCCUAUGAUGAAGUACGUAAUCUUUAUUAUAUUAUUUUACAUUAACCAUCUUUUUUUUCAAAUUGUUUUAUUUUUUAUUUUACUUUAAGUUCUGGGAUACAUGUGCUGACCAUGCAGGUUUGGUACAUAUGUAUACAUGUAACCAUCAUUUUAAUAUCUCACACAUGUAAAUGCACAUCUUUGUAGUUACCAAUCAAAUGUAUGUGAGGCAAUGAAAGGCAUUGAGCAGUUACAGUAAAGGGCAGACAUCAGGCCUCUGCCAGUAUGUACCUGCUGUGCCUUCCUGCCUGCCCUAUUUCUUUGUUUUCAGUGUGCAUGCCAGUCACUGCUGCUUCUGGAGACAGGAUGGAAGGAUACAUGUAUGUGUACAUUUAUGGAGAAAACCAAUUUAUAGAUGUAUCAGAGCUCUAAGGGAUUCUCUUUCACUUCCUUGGGACUCCCAAGCAGAGGAAUUAAUAGAUUAGGAGGGUCUUUUGGGGGGUUGGUUUAAAUUUUCAGGGCGAUAGAGGCUAACUUCUCGUUGGCCUUCAUGAAUUUUCAAUAUAUCAUCUUUUCGCUGA